CCCACCAUCUCCAUCCCCGCUCUGGGCUCACGCUCUGGAUAAGGACGGCGCGGGGGCGGUUGUCUGAUGACAAUUUCAUUCUCGUUUUGUCAUUUUUCUCAUUUAGCUCAUUUUUGUCAUUUUAGUCCAUUGUUAGGCAUGCUCGAGGACAACUCCUCCGGAGAGCGGUAGUGGCGGAGGAGGGGCCGGGAGCGUGCGUUAACCCGGAAGAAGUGAACCAGGAAGUGAACGUGAUCUCGGGUACUCACAGUUCUUUCCUGAUCUUCCCCGCCGCCUCCUGUAUUGCCUCUUUAUGGAAUCACUCCAUAUACUGAGUUACACAGCAUGGUUUGCCCGUGCUGCUGCCCCGCGGGCUGUCGCUUCUGACCUGCCUACACUCAGAACUUUCCCCAAAGCAUCAGAGUAAUACUGUUACUGUGAUGGGUAAUGGAGAAGUCGUGCUGUUCUCAGGUGUAGUUAACCUUGGAGAGUAAACAUCUUGUUUUGUUUUGUUUUCCUUAAUGUUGAGAUUCAUGACCUUGAAAAUUAUGCAUUCUACUACUGUUCCUAAAAUGGAAAUUUUAGCAAUAAGUAUUCGUACAAACAUAUAUUUGUCAUCCUUUUAUUCUGUCUGUUAGCAAAUGGAUACACUUUCUCUAACGUGCUUGAAAUACGGGGGUGGUGGAGUGUAACGUUUGUGACAGCUGGCCAUUGGUGCUUUCUUCAACAGUUCUUUUAAUAAUGUGAUGCAGUAUCCUAAAAUCUAUCAGUAGAACUCUGGAAACUGAAUAUUUUAAAGACCAUUCUGACUAUUUUAUUUCCUAGGUGAUAAUGCUAAGUUAACAGACUUAUAGUGAACAAAUGAGCUAAUAUAUCAAUGCACCUCCUAGCAUAGUAGGAUCACUGGAGACAGUAAAGUUUGAUUUUGAUAAAUGUUGAUCCUUCUUUUUUUGAGUUGAGUCUCACUGUGUUGCCCAGGCUGGCCUUGAACUCCUUGGCUCAAGUGAUCCUCCUGCCUCAGUCUCCUGGGUAGCUGGGACAAUAGGUGCAUGCUACUGUGCGUGGCUUGACCCUUAUUUCAACUUUGAACCUUAGAGUUUUCUUAGAACACUUUAUAUUCUCCCUUUCUUACUCAGUAAGACCAUUGUGUACUUUUGUUAGCUCUUGAUUAUCUCUGUUGGAGGGGAGGAGAACAGAAAAUUAUUGUACACAGCCAAUUUCACCUAACCUGUAAUUUUUUAAACUAAUCUUUUUUUAUGAUUAGGAAAGUAUUCCAUGCUACAUGUGCAAGAAACUUGGAAAACACUGAAAAGUAGAAAAAAUAGCAAGCAAAAGGUUCAAGCGAUUAUCCUGCCUCAGCUUCCCGAGCAGCUAGGACUACAGGAUCUCAGCUAAACGGGAAGCAUUUUUGAAAAGUGAUUGCACAAUUGAGAGUGAAAAUUACUGAGUCCUGAACAGGCAACUUACAUUCUAAUACCAGCUCUGUCUCCAUCCAGCCGACUGAAUAGUCGUGAUUAAGUUACUUGACUUCCUUGGAUAUCUAGAUCCUUAAAGUUAAAGAAUUAUACAAGAUAAUAAUAUUUUCUUCAAACUUUAGAAAAUGACUUUAUGAACCGCCUUAAGUUUGUAUGUUUUCAUAGCUUUCAAGAGCUUGUUUACACACUCAAUUCUAGAUUCUAGAUACUUUCUAGAAAAUAACUGACUUAACUCAUUCAAUUGAUAUAUUUGUUAGUUGUACUCCUACUCAUAUGCUUCAGUUAAUUAUAUAUGUUGAACAGGUAGGAAGCAGUGCUGUUUUUAUUUAUUUUAAUAUGUUAUUCAUACAUUUGAAGAAUUAUGUUCUUUCUGUAGGCAGCUGAAUUUUUUUUUUUUUUGAGACGAAGUCUUGGUAUUGUCCCCCUUGCUGGAGUGCAAUGGCAUGAUCUCGGCUCACUGCAACCUCUGCCUCCUGGGUUCAGGCAAUUCUCCUGCCUCAGACUCCUGAGUAGCUGGGAUUACAGGCGCCUGCCACCACGCCCGGAUAAUUUUUGUAUUUUUAGUAGAGACAGUGUUUCACUAUGUUGGCUGGGCUGGUCUCGAACUCCUGCCCUCAGGUGAUCCGCCUGCCUCAGCCUCCCAAAGUGCUGGGAUUACUGGCGUGAGCCACUGCUGCCAGCCGGCAGUUGAAUUUUAAGACUGUGGAGCUGGCUGAGGCAGUAGAUGAAACAAGAUUUCUUGAUGUUCCUUCCAGGUUUAUUAUGCAUGUAUCUUUAGAGAUGAUUUUUUUUUAAAGACUGUGUUUAUUGUAUUUCAGAUGCUGAGAUGAAUCGUCACCUGUGUGUUUGGCUUUUUAGACAUCCAUCUCUUAAUGGUUACCUCCAGUGUCACAUCCAGCUCCAUUCUCAUCAAUUUAGACAGAUACAUCUUGAUACAAGGCUGCAAGUUUUUAGACAAAACAGGAAUUGCAUUCUUCAUCUGUUAAGUAAGAAUUGGUCCAGGAGAUAUUGCCAUCAAGACACCAAGAUGCUCUGGAAGCAUAAAGCACUACAGAAAUAUAUGGAGAACCUGAGUAAGGAGUACCAAACACUUGAGCAAUGUCUGCAGCAUAUCCCUGUGAAUGAGGAAAACCGAAGGUCCUUGAACAGAAGGCAUGCUGAGUUGGCACCUCUUGCAGCCAUUUACCAAGAAAUUCAGGAGACUGAACAAGCAAUUGAAGAAUUAGAAUCAAUGUGUAAAAGCCUAAAUAAACAAGAUGAAAAGCAGUUACAAGAACUUGCACUGGAAGAAAGGCAAACCAUUGAUCAAAAAAUCAACAUGUUGUACAAUGAGCUUUUCCAGAGCCUUGUGCCAAAGGAGAAAUAUGACAAAAAUGAUGUUAUUUUAGAGGUGACAGCUGGAAGGACUACUGGAGGUGACAUCUGCCAACAAUUUACCCGAGAAAUAUUUGACAUGUACCAGAAUUAUUCGUGCUAUAAACACUGGCAAUUUGAACUUCUGAAUUAUACACCAGCAGAUUAUGGUGGACUACAUCAUGCAGCCGCCCGAAUUUCCGGUGACGGUGUCUAUAAGCAUUUGAAGUAUGAGGGUGGGAUUCACCGAGUUCAGCGCAUCCCCGAGGUGGGCCUGUCCUCAAGGAUGCAGCGCAUUCACACAGGAACGAUGUCGGUUAUUGUCCUUCCUCAGCCAGAUGAGGUGGAUGUGAAAUUGGACCCCAAGGAUUUGCGAAUAGAUACAUUUCGAGCCAAAGGAGCAGGAGGGCAGCAUGUUAAUAAAACUGAUAGUGCCGUCAGACUUGUCCACAUCCCCACAGGGCUAGUAGUAGAAUGCCAACAAGAAAGAUCACAGAUAAAAAAUAAAGAAAUAGCCUUUCGUGUGUUGAGAGCUAGACUCUACCAGCAGAUUAUUGAGAAAGACAAGCGUCAGCAACAAAGUGCUAGAAAACUGCAGGUGGGAACAAGAGCCCAGUCAGAGCGAAUUCGGACAUAUAAUUUCACCCAGGAUAGAGUCAGUGACCACAGGAUAGCAUAUGAAGUUCGUGAUAUUAAGGAAUUUUUAUGUGGUGGGAAGGGCCUGGAUCAGCUAAUUCAGAGACUGCUUCAAUCAGCAGAUGAAGAAGCCAUUGCUGAACUUUUGGAUGAACACCUUAAAUCAGCAAAAUAAAUACUAACUUAUUAUUAUUUAUGAUUAUAUAAAUGAAAUGGACCUAUAUCAAGAGGCAGACUGAAGCUUGGAAAUCAUUAUGAAUAUUUGUAAAUUACAGCUUUAAGAACACAUUACACAUAAAUAUAUGUUUUGUAAUUAAUCGAAGUCACAUUUCCUGACCUAAGAAUUUAUUUUAGGUUUCCUGUAAAGUACAAUCCAACUCAUCAAGUAGAAAAUAAGCAUGCAUCAUUGAAAAGAGAAAGUAUUGAGAAUUGAUUGUGUCAUUUAGGACAAGUCACUUGUUCUCUUUAUAUGCCUUUUUUCCCCAGCCAUCUAUGAAUUAAUUUAAAUAUAUUUUUAAUCUACUACUUCAGGAAAAUAUGGUAAAAUUUAGUAAAAUAUGAAUUUUAGACUUCCUUAUAAACCUUUUAUUUAAAUACAAAGUACCUUGGCCUAUAGUGGAUGCUUAUGCCUGUAAUCCCAGUGCUUUGAAGGGCCAAAGGGGGAAGAUCUCUUGAGGUAAGAAUUUGAGACCAGCCUGGGCAAAAUAGACCCCAUGUCUACAAAAAAACUCAAAACAUAAAGAAAAACCAUAAUACUGUUAAUCAUGUUAAAGUUAAGACUUAGACUGCAACUUUUAAAUAAAAAUUAUGAAGAAUAUGAGUCAUUCAAUAACAAUGAGCAUCUGGGUACAGACAGUAAAGCCCUUUGAUUGCUGUAUGAAUUCCACACUAUAUAAACAAUAAGCUGAUAUUUUAAAUAGA